AAUGAGCACCCUAAUCUGUGGUUAUCAGGCUCUGAUAACCGUUCCUUUGGGGAUGUAGCAACCAAGAAGGAGACUCAAGCAGAUGGAUUACCAGUAACAUUCAAUUUCUUGAUCUGGGAAUUGAUUACAUAGGGUUUUCAAUUUAUGAUGAUCAACUGACCUGUACACUUAAGAUUUGUGCAGUUUUAUAGUAUGUACAUUUUACAUUAAUGAAAAUUAAAGUUUUUAAUUUGAUUAAAUUGAGAAAGACAUGGGAACCCACACAAUAUGGCAGACCUCUGCAGUUUGUAGUCAAGCUCUUACAGUGCUUAGUGUCUAUUUCACUCCUCCUACACUCUCAACUGGAGUUUUCCAGGCUCCUGUCAGAGGUCAUCCUUGUAUCUUAGUUGUCAAAUCCAUGAACCUUUUUUAGUCAUCUCUUUCUUGACAUCUAAUUUUAUUUAACCUCUACUUUAUUAAAAAGUUUAGCUCUUUUUAACUUCCCAGUAGGCUACUCACUCUGUCUUCUACUGUUUGAACUAUUCCGAGUUACUCUUCUUCAAGAUUUCCUUUUUCCAUGUGCCUCUACAUUUUGACCCAUGGAUUUUAUUAUCCUUUCUUUUGUAAUCUUUCUGUAUCUUUUUUCUGCCUGUUUAUUUAUUGCUAUGGUUUAACCCACUUAUAUAAUAAAAACCUGUAAGAGCAUUAAUACUGAGUCGGUUUUUCUUCGAGAGUUCCAAACCCAAAUUUCACUGUUCCAUAGGAAUCUCAUCUGAAUAAAUUCAAAAGUUAACUUUUCAUGUCCCCAGACCUGCUAUAGUUUUUUAUAUUGUCUGCCUUUGUUAAUAUAUCAUCAUGUAAUUGUCCAAACCAGAAACCUGGUAUUAUCCUGGAUUUUUUUGUUUGUGUUUGGUUUGUUAAUUUGUCCGUUAUCUCAUUUUCUCUCCACAAUAACAUGGUUACGUCGAUUCUCCUCUUUAUAUGUCUGUUAUGUCAUCCAUGACACUUGCCAUCCAUGACAUUUUUACCUUAGUUCAUUAUUUCUUACACAGGCAUUUUGAUUAGAGCACAACUGGUCACCCUGACUCCAGUUUUAAACCCCAAGACUCAGUCCCACAACAAAAUCAUAAUAGAACUGUUCAUUUCAUCUGAGUCUUUACUAGCCUGUACAUACUUCUGUCUUAGAACCUGCAACACUUGUAAAAUAUCCUUGAGUUUGCUUACCUAUCUAUCUAUUAUAGACUUAAACUGGGACCUUAUUUUAUUGACCUCAGAAGCCACUGUGCUUGCAGCAUUUUAGAUGCUAAGCAUAUGGCUAUUGAAAGGAUAUCUCUGUGAUUUUUAGCUAUUUGUAUUUUUGAGUUUAUCAGUCUCCCUUAUCAGACUAAGCUCAUUAACAGUCAGGUCAAUGUACUUAAUCUAAUACUCAAUAAAUGUUUGCUUAAUGAAUAAAUGCAUGUAGUAGAAUUAAGUUUGGCUGAAAUAAACUUUGAUUAGGAACUUGUAAAGGACUAAAAGAUUAAUAAAAAGAGCUUUAAAGUAGCUCAAAGGAAGAGAAUCAUAUAAAAAUUCAAUGGAAUAGUUGUGAGAUAGUGAAUUCAUUAUAGGAAAAGGAAAGAUUUAUUUCUUAUCCUUUUUUUAAUGAUGAAAAAGCUUAUUUGGGAAAAUUCUGUUAAUAUUCUUUUCCAAACAUGAACAGACUGAAGAAUUACCAAUCAGAUAGCUAUCAAUCUUAUGAUAUUUUAGAACAAUACAUAAAAAUAAACCUACAUAUAUCAGUGGCAUCAGAUCUAGGUGUUUCAUAAGGUGGCGAAGAAAAAUAAAGAUUAGUGGAUCACACACAUGUCUAGCCAAGCAAGGUAGUAGAAAAAAAAUAAGGGAUGGGUACAAAGAACAUUUGUAUUAAAUAAGCUGCUAGGGGAAACAGCAACAUUGUCUCUAGAAAGGAUAAUACUUGAUGAAUUAAUUGGAAUGUGUUGAGAGGAAAGUUAGAAAAAUAUAUAGAGAGGAGAUAGAUACAUGGUUUAAAAUUAUUUAGACAUUCAUAAAUCUUUGACAGUGUAUAAUACCAAAGACCCCAAAACCUAACCCCUUUUUUAUGAAAAAAAAAUUGGCUUACAAAAUAGAAAAUAAAGUGUGUAGAAAAUACAGGUACUUCUCUGAGUAAAAAUAGUUUCUUGGGAAGAUCUGUUCUAGGUACAUAUUUUAUAAAAAUUUGAAUAUCUUCAAGUUUGAAGUUGAAUUAAACCUUACUGGAUAUUGAAUAUAUAAGGAAAGAGGAAUAAAAACAAAAUUUCUUUAUCUAUGUAAGUGUGAAGAAAGAUGCUUUUAAUAAUCUAAGAGCUACGUGUCUUUAAUAUUUUAGUGGACCAAGGGAGACUCUGGGAUUUUGAAAGCAAUUGCUUAUGGUUAUUAUUUUUGUUAGAAUUGGUGACAUAUUGCUGGAGUUAGAGUUUCUCAUUAGCUGCUAAGAAGCAUAUGUUAUAAAAUAAUUUAAAAUUGCAUAUUCAUAUGCACAUUUUUCCACAAGUGUUUUACAUCUCUCUACAGGAGUGUCUUCCUUUUUAAAUAGAUGUCUGCUUUUGGAGGCUCUAAUUAGUUAUCUUUUCUUUGUUUUUACAUUCCAUUUUAUUUACAACAGAAAACUGUGCUUAAUGCUGUGUAUACUGAUACUGAAUUGCAAUCUACCUUCUUUCCUUUUAUUUUUUAUAUGUUUCAACUUGAAGAUUAUAUUGCAAGAUGAAGGUCAGCAGGAUACAAAAUGACAAAAAGUGAUUAUAAUUAAUAUGUUAGAUGAUGAUAUGAUAGUUAUAAUGCGAACCAUGAUAAUUAGAGAAAACCAGUGAAUUUUUAUAUUAAAAUUUUAAUAAUGUCUGUCACAUUGUUAAUUCAGGUUCUAAGUGUUGUAUUUAAUUCUGCAUCAUUAUUUUAAGCUCUAAUUUUUUUUGUCAAAAAAUGGCUACUAAGACUUAAGAGUCAUUAAUAUGAAAAUAUGUCUGCAUAAUCUCUUUGUCAAAGGUAGAGAAGGAUGACUGAAUUACUCAUUAUAGCAUGUAAGGAAUGUGACUACUGUAGCAAAAUGAAUAGAGAACAUAUUCUUCAGAUAUAAACAAAUCCUAUAACUCAAACAUUAAAAGUUCAGUUUACCCAUCACUAGCUCCUGAUUCUCCAGCCUUUGUAGAACAGUAACUGAGGAGGGUUAUUGAAAACUCCUAGUGGACAAGACAAUGAUAAAGAGGGCCCUGUAUUUCUGCCUGAUUAUUGGGAGAACAGUUCUGAGCAUAAACACUUCAUUUCAAAAUUUAGCAAGUCAGAGCUGUAUAAUUUUUCUUUAUCUAAGUGUCAUGUUGAAAAGUAGCAGAUUUUGAAGCUUGUAUUUUUUUUCUUAAGAAUCAAAUUUAAUAAAGGUAAUGGCAAGAUAAUUCAAUACGAUUCUUUUUUCCUCUCUGCUUAAGUAACAUGAAUUCCCAAAACAGUAUGUGGAAUAAAAAUCAUUACAGUUUAGAUCAUUUUCUAUUAUCAUAGAAGAAAAAAAAGGUACAGUGUUAAAGGGGAGAAAAAUUGCUGACUUUGAAUACAGUAGACCUAGGUUUGAAUCCUGGCUUUACCAGUGAUUAGCAGUACUCCUUGUUAUUUAUUUAACAUUCCUGAGUAUCAGUUUCUUCAUAGGAAAAACUUAGAUGGAAGACUUUCCCUUGCAUACAUAUUACAAUGAGUGCAAACACCUAGUACAAUAUCUAAAACCCAGAAAUUGCUUCAAGUGGUAGCAUUCACUAUUGUUACUGGUGUUGGAGUAACCAGCCCCCAAAUGGCCACCAGUGAGCCACCUCUGGAUAAUUAUGCCUUGGUAUAAUCCUCUCCUCCUGAGUGUAAGCUAGGCAAAGUGGCUCACAUCUAAUGAAUAGACUAUGGAAGAAGUAAUGGUGAAUCACUUCCAAGAUUAGGUUAUAAAUGACUGCAGGUUCCAGUGCAGGCAGUCUUUCUGUCUGUCUCAUCAGUCACUAUGGAGGAAGCCAGAUGACAUGUCAUAGCCAACAUGUGAAAAGAGCCCACAUGGUGAGGACCACAUCUCUGUCCAACAGAUAGCAGGAUCCAAAGCUUGCCAACACGUCCUAAUUGGGCUUUGAAGCAGAGCCUCCCCUAGUCAAACCUUUUGACAGCUCCAGCCAACAGUUUGAAACCUCACAAAAAUCUGAUCUUGAACAACCCAGUUAAACUUCUCUCAUAUUUCUACCCUUAGAAAUUGUAAGACUAUCACUGACUUUUGUUUUAAGCUGUGGAUUUGUUAUGUAGCAAUGGCUAACUUAAACAAUAUUAUCAUUCUUGAAGUUGUUUAUGAAGUACAAUUGAAAAAUCGUAUUUUAAAGAGUCUUUCCAAGGGUUUUCAAGUAUUGAAAUUUAUUCUUACGUAUAUACACAAUCUUUAUUUUUUUUACUUUUCACAAAGGGAUGUACGAGUAAUUUAAUGGCAUAUUUUAAAAAAUCUCUAUUUCUCCACAGCUAAAAUAGAUUUUGGUAAAAAUCACUUCACUGUAAGGAUAACUAACAAAAUAGAGCAGGACAAGGCCAGAGGGAGUAUGUGAAAAUAGUCAAAGCAAUUUCAGAGGGAAAUUCUACCUCUGCAGAAGACAUAUCCCUUGCAGCAAUAAACGACAUAAUGUAAUGAAUGGAAUCAUUCAUAAACAGUUCAAUUCUCAUGUGUUAACCUUGACCAUCCAAGGUUGUUUGAUCAAAAUAAAACAUACUAAAACUUUCAACAAUGAGAGAAGAGGGGCAAAUGUUUCAUCACUUUUAUAUGUGUUGUGGUAUUCCAAUGAAGAAAGUGAGAGGGGUAAAAAUUAUUAUGGUUUGUUAGGGGAACUAUUAAGAAUUAAGCUACGUGUGGGUGAAUAGUGACAGAUGGGUUGGAUAGGAAAGUCUAAACCAGAUUAUGAAAGGUAGUUUUUAAUGAGUAAUUUCAACUGUAAUAAGAAACUAUUUUAGGAUUUCGACCAAUAAAGUACUGUGAUAAUAAUGAUGUUUUGUUAACACUCCAUUAAUAUGGUAUAGGAUGGUAGAUGUUGUCUAGCAGAGCACAGUAAAUUCCUUGGAGACUCUUGUAUCUCCUAUGAAUAGUGUGUGUUUCUGGUUGGGCAUACAGUGGACAAUAUAUUCUUGCUGUAUGUUAUUAAAAUUCAUGGAAUCUAGCAGUCCAUGAGCAAACAUCAAAGGAAAUGAUAGUCCUUUUUGGUAUCAACAUUGAUUCUUUUCUUGUUCAUUUGUGUCAUAAGAUUACAUUUAUAUCUUUUACGUUAGUUUAGGUGAUGAAAUUUAUGGAAGAUUGUGUGUGUGUGUGUGUGUGUGUGUGUAUAAUACUAUAGAUAGUCAUACUCAGCAUAGGGAAGAAAGACUUUGUAUUCAAACAGACCUGGAUACAAACUUGCCUGUACCACUUACCAGCUUUUAAGUUAUUUACACCAAGCCUUUAUUUCUAAAAGCGCUAUCUGGGGUGAUUACGUCUACCUUAAAAGAUUUUUGUAUGAAGAGUCUGGGCCAUAAUGGGUACCCCAUGAAUGUUGCUAUUAUCCUUUAGUAAAUGAAGCAACUGCUUCCCAUUAAUUAGGUUCUUUGCAAUCAAGACAUAAUUAAAAGGAAAAGAAAUCUCACAAUUAGGGAUUUACAUCCCUUGCCUUUUUUUGAGUCAAUAUUUCUAAUACAUUUUUAAGUGUUCCUGUUUGCUGGAAGAAAUUUCCAAGACUACAGUGAAGUUAUUAUACAAAUUUAUUUCCUUAGAAUCUGUAAAAAUUAUGAAACAUAAGUGCUUUAUUCAUUGCUCUACUUACAAACCACACACACACACACACACACACACACACACGUAUUUCACAAGACAUUUAGGUUAUGGUUCCCAUCCAAGUCAUGUAUCCUAGAAAGAAAACAUUCCUCAGAACAUUUGAAAUUCUUAACCACGUUGCCAGCAGAAUAGUCUGCCAACUCCUAAGCGAAAACCCAGGCCUUUCAAAUAUUUGUUUACUAAAUAAAAAUAAGACAAGAUAUUUUGCUGCACCUACACUGAAAUAAUUUAAAUAUGAAUUUUAGUUACAGAAUAUGUGGAAUAAACCACAGACGAAUGUAAAGUAUAUCUAUCAUUAAAAAAAGAAACGUCCUUUAAUUUUCAUUUCCAUUUUUAUCUUGCUAUUUCAGUUCUGCCUCUCUAAAUCCAAACUAAAGAAAGCAGAUAAGGAAGACACUUAGGUUACAUCAUAUCCUUUUGCAAGAUGCUGAAAUAUGUUUUAAAAUUUGCUGUGUGAAUACUAGGCCAUGCAUGAAUCAUCUGAUUUUAUUGGUAUGUGCCAUGUACACGUCUAUUUUAAAGUCCACUACUUUACUAAAAUAUUUUGAUAAACUGGCUCAGUUAAUCCUCGCUAAUUUUGACUGCACAAAUAAUUACUGAAUUUGUGAUUUUGCAUAUUAUUUUUUAAAUUCAUACAUUAAGGAUAAUUUAUCAAGCCAAACUUUACAUGUAUUACAUUGAUUCUUAGAAAACAAAUAUGAGCUCAAGUUACUGCUGAAAUGAGAAUUGCAGAAAGGCAAACACAUUUGUCUUUUCUUAUUAGCAUCAAUAGCUUUAAUCAAGCUGGGAAAUCUUAUUUAAAAUAAAUAACUCUUUGUCAGAAAUUCCUGAGUUGUUGAUUUCAAGCUCUGGGUAAUCACUCGAUAGGCCAACAGUAAAUUAAUGCCAAGUGUUCCACUGUCAAGUAUAAGGUUCACAGUAUGCUAAAAAAGAAAUAUAUAUAUACAAUUUUUGUUUGUCUAUGAAUUUUUAUACAUAUAUGUGAAACCUACUCUAAAAAAUACAUCAUUAUAUUAAGGUACUAAGGUUAUAAUUUUUUUAUAUUUUGUAUACUCAUUUUGGUCUAGUUUUGCUAUUGUAUAUCUUUAUGAAAAAAUACAUGCUUGGGAGAGUAUGGAAAGAGGGUUGCUUUAGAGAAAAACUAAAAAUAAAAACUCUAAAAUAUUAAUAGAAAAAACAACCUUUUCUUUUCUUUUUUUUAAUAUUUUUUGGCAAAACAGGCUCUUCCAGAAAAGAGCUUCACUUAGGGAACACAGGGAAAUGAUCAGGAAAUCUGAAUGUGUCAAGAUAAAGUUAUCACACUUCUUUACUAUACUUGCUGUUGUUUAUGUAUUAAUGUUUUAUAAAAACAAAUUUGUUUAUAAGUUUUUAAUCUCUGUACAAACACUUGAAUAUAGAGGGUUGUUUUCAUUAGCUUUUGCUUUGUUUUCUAAAAACAGGAAAUUGUUUAUACCUAGGCCAUCAGGUCUCUAAUAUAAAAAAAUGAAUUAGGUGGCAAUGAACUGAAAAUAGCAAAAUUUGGAAAACAACUAAAAUUCUAUCUUCCCUCAACUUUUAAAUUCUAUUACUAAUUUAAUCUCCUACUUGCAGAAAAUAAGCAGUUUACUUGAAUAUAGGUUAGUUGCUUCUAUGUAUGUAAAUAUAUCCAGGUGCAGAGAAUCAUGUUACAUGGGUUUACUCUGAGGGCCAUACACACCUACUCUAGUAACUCAAUACACAACUAUAACAUCUGUAACAUCUUUUCACUUGAUUUCUGGUUAAUUCUCUCUUGCUACUUCCUUGAUAUUGGAAUUUGUACAUCCCUUCUGUGAGGGUCUCUAUUCUAGUCCUCAAGAGCUGGGAAUUUAAACCCAAUCAUUCUCCAACAUUUAUUCUUCUUUAGGAGGUGGAAAUGAACCAGAAAACCUAUCUAAGUCUGUUUAUGUGCCCAAAUGAGUCUGACCACCAUCCAGAUCUUUAGGAUCCCUCCUUCCACAGCCUAUAAAUACUUUCCCAGUAUUUUCUUGGGGAUCCAUAGUCAUGAUUGGUUUUACUAAGUAUAGAGAGGAGGUCUAUCAAUGUGAUUAGAAGAUCUUUUUUUGCUAAUCAUUGCUAAUCAAAAUAAGGCUCCUCCCUUCCCAUAGAGACAGGAAGAUGAGGACUCUAUCUUGCUUGAUGAUUACAUUCCAAAGAAUGGCUCCCAAAUCCCAGAGAAAGACAUUCCUAGGUUGUAAAACUGUCAAGAGUCUGCGAUAAUAUGUACAUCUGAAAGUAACAAAGAAAGGAUUUAUAUUUGAAAGUUUCCUAUAGUAAAUGUUUUAAGAAAAGGGAAGUCUGGAGCUUAUGGUCAGGAAAAAAACCUGUCUAAAGUUUAGUCAAGCUGUAGGGAAAAUUAGGGCCAUCUAAGAUAUAAGCUACCAAAUGCAUCUUAAAUUCAAUUGCUGUGUAAGUUACCCUUUAUUUAUGCUUUAAUCAGAAUUGUUUCUUUAGUGUAGGAUCAGAAGUUUUUUCAAUGUAAAAUAAAAAAAGUUUCUGGUGUCCAAAUGUGUAUGCUUAGAAAGCAGGAAUUUUGUGAACAAAAUACACUAAUUGUUUUGCUAAUUAUUCCUCUCAUAUGCAAUUGUGCAAGCAUGUACUGGCUUCCAACUUUAUGAAGGAUUCAAAAGGCUGAUAGGAAACAGAGGCCGUUCUCCGCAGCAUGCAGGAAAUGACUUAUUUCUUGUAGCAGUCCAUGAACUGGGACAUGCUCUGGGAUUGGAGCAUUCCAAUGACCCCACUGCCAUCAUGGCUCCAUUUUACCAGUACAUGGAAACAGACAACUUCAAACUACCUAAUGAUGAUUUACAGGGCAUCCAGAAGAUAUAUGGUCCACCUGACAAGAUUCCUCCACCUACAAGACCUCUACCGACAGUGCCCCCACACCGCUCUAUUCCUCCGGCUGACCCAAGGAAAAAUGACAGGCCAAAACCUCCUCGGCCUCCAACCGGCAGACCCUCCUAUCCCGGAGCCAAACCCAACAUCUGUGAUGGGAACUUUAACACUCUAGCUAUUCUUCGUCGUGAGAUGUUUGUUUUCAAGGACCAGUGGUUUUGGCGAGUGAGAAACAACAGGGUGAUGGAUGGAUACCCAAUGCAAAUUACUUACUUCUGGCGGGGCUUGCCUCCUAGUAUCGAUGCAGUUUAUGAAAAUAGCGACGGGAAUUUUGUGUUCUUUAAAGGUAACAAAUAUUGGGUGUUCAAGGAUACAACUCUUCAACCUGGUUACCCUCAUGACUUGAUAACCCUUGGAAGUGGAAUUCCCCCUCAUGGUAUUGAUUCAGCCAUUUGGUGGGAGGACGUCGGGAAAACCUAUUUCUUCAAGGGAGACAGAUAUUGGAGAUAUAGUGAAGAAAUGAAAACAAUGGACCCUGGCUAUCCCAAGCCAAUCACAGUCUGGAAAGGGAUCCCUGAAUCUCCUCAGGGAGCAUUUGUACACAAAGAAAAUGGCUUUACGUAUUUCUACAAAGGAAAGGAGUAUUGGAAAUUCAACAACCAGAUACUCAAGGUAGAACCUGGAUAUCCAAGAUCCAUCCUCAAGGAUUUUAUGGGCUGUGAUGGACCAACAGACAGAGUUAAAGAAGGACACAGCCCACCAGAUGAUGUAGACAUUGUCAUCAAACUGGACAACACAGCCAGCACUGUGAAAGCCAUAGCUAUUGUCAUUCCCUGCAUCUUGGCCUUAUGCCUCCUUGUAUUGGUUUACACUGUGUUCCAGUUCAAGAGGAAAGGAACACCCCGCCACAUACUGUACUGUAAACGCUCUAUGCAAGAGUGGGUGUGAUGUAGGGUUUUUUCUUCUUUCUUUCUUUUGCAGGAGUUUGUGGUAACUUGAGAUUCAAGACAAGAGCUGUUAUGCUGUUUCCUAGCUAGGAGCAGGCUUGUGGCAGCCUGAUUCGGGGCUGACCUUUCAAACCCAGAGGGUUGCUGGUCCUGCACAUGAGUGGAAAUACACUCAUGGGGAAGCUUCCAUGAUGCACAGUAUCUGCUGUUCUUCAGUCCUUUGUCUUUCUUUGUCAUUCAGUUCUAGGCCUUUCCUCUGCACGCUCAAUGCCCAGUAAAAUUUCAGGAUUAACUAAAGAAGAGGAGAAAAAGAAGAAAAGAUUCUUCUUAAAAGUUUCUAAUGUUAUUUUCCUUCUGAAGUCUGAGCCCAUUUCUGGGGGGAGAAAAAAAAAGCAAAUCAGAAAACCCACGGUUUUUCUUUUUUUCUUUUUUUCUUUUUUUCUUUUUUUGCUUUAAAACAAAGGGAAAAAAGAGUUUAAACAAAAAACCCACAAUUGAACUUCCAGGAAAGUGUGAAGACCCAAAACAGCUUUGUCUCCAAAGAAGAUAGCUCUCUGACUGCUUUGGAUAGUCUCCUACGCACCAUUUUGUCAGGUGGGAGAUUUGGAAUACACAUGCAGGACGUUAGACUGUUGGGACAGCCAUUUUCCAACAACCAAGGGGCCAAAAUAUCUGCAAUAUAGUAACAGCCUUAAUAAUACAUCCAUUUUUCGUUUUAUACAGCUGUUCUCAGCUAUGUCCUCAGUGUUUCAUCGCAUUUAUAUUCAUAGCUAUUUUCAAACACGACCUUUUAAUUGUUUUUGAAGUAUUUCUAAACCCCUUCUUUCCACCUUACUCCUCCAUCAUUGUGAUAAUCUUCCCAAGUUGUAUUAGGCCAUUGCCCCAGGCCUUCCAUGGGUCUGUCAGGAAUAUUCGUUACAAAGCAGAGCAAGAAGCAGUAUGUCUCUGAAGUGGAUUACAGUGGCAGUUAUUUUACAAGGAUUUGUGACACUAGUAACAUACCCGUGUAACCCUUUGAGAACUAUCAGACCAGCUUUCAGAGUCUUAGGAUUGUCGGUCUUGCGAUCUGAUAAAUUAUAGAACUGGGCAAUGGUAAAAACAGUCACAAGUUCAAGAAGUUCAGGUUUUUAAAACAGAUAUCCUAUAAUGUCAUAUAAUUUUUAAAUGAUUUACAAGACUACAUAAAUGUGUUUAUAACAAACAGAAAUGAUGUUACUUGCCAAAAUUUUUCUGGCAAAUAAAAAAGGUAUUUUAUUAAGAUUCUCAUAAAUCUGAAAUUUUAUUUGAAAAACUGAUAAUAGCCUAAGUCUUCUUUUCUUUUUUUUAGGCAUACUGAAUUUCUGUUUUAAAAUCCAUUGCAUGAAAAUUCAAUUUGCCUUGGUAUAUGCAGUUAGCAUUGCCAUUUUAAAAAUGAAUUAAAACGGUGACUCUGAAGUUGCAUGAAUAUCCUCCAGUGCAUUACCUAUUGCAUGUCCACCAUAGUUCUCAAAGGGUUAGUGUGGCUUCUGGCAUUUAGCCGUCCAUUUGAUCACUGACAGAGCCAAGAGACCACCAAAGCAUUUCAUUGUUGAGUGUAAUUUGUCCUAACAGCAGUAUUGUCAUUUUCAUGUGACCUGCAGAGCAGGUUUGUAUCAAUAUUUUUUUCCUAGAGAAAAGUCAGCAACUGACAGACCUCUUUAUUGAUUUUUAGGAGCUGCUUCUUGCAGUGAAAGGCUUUACAGCCACUGGGCUGUGAACUUAUUAGAGAUGGUCAGAAUGAAUGCACCCCAUGAGUCAGACAUUGGCUUUGUGUGAAAGCCAGCUUUGAGGGGAUUAGCUUUUGAAACAAUGAACAGCUUGCCUUGAACUUGAUUAUUGAUCUAUUGACUGUCAUUAACAACAACUUAAACAUUGUCUUCUGUGAAAAUUUUCCUUGAAGAGUCCUGUUCUAUGUCUUUGCCCUUUGACCUUUAACUUGCAAACUGGCACAAACUGAAGGAAAUCUGGUGUUGCUUCUCCAUUGGAUUAGUUGUUCUCUAAAACCUAGUAAGCAUGAGCUGUUUCCUUAGAGUGGAGAGAGUGGUGAUGGCAGAUCUGCAGAUGGACACUUUGCUCUUUACAUGCACACUCUGAAAAUGCCCUAUAGGUAGAAGUGAAUUUUAAUUUCAUUUUAAUAUAAUUUCAAGUCUAAAUUCAUCAUUUUAGUACAAAUUACAAAAACUAUAGGAAAAAAAAAACCUCAAAUACUUGAAUGGCCAGUGUGGCUUUUAUAUAAAGCAGGAAUUUUAUACUAGUAAAAAUUUCUUACUCAUUUGCUAAUACACAUUUCCAGAUGAUUUUUAAUGAGUGUAGGUAUACAUUCUUAUUUGGAAAUGGAUAGUUUGGCUGCCUUGAAUUUAUAUUUAUACUCAACGUAGCAUGAAAAUUAGAAUGCCUUUUGGUUAAACUACAUGUUUAUGAUUUGGUUGGGGAAAAUAUUUUAUAAUUGUGGGUGGCAUGCUGCAAAGCCUUGCAGAUUGUUAUUUCUUACAACCUGAGCGUAUAUAGUAUGAGCCUAAGAAAAAAGAAGAGUAAGAAAAGAAGAAUGGCUUUACAGUAAAAUAUCAUACAAUGCAGACAAUAUUUUAAGAGGAUAUUGGAGAUUAUGUACGCAAGGGCCAAGAAAGCAAGAAAUGAGAACCAGAGUCAGCCCUGUAGCUUUACUUCAGUGCUUCCAUUCUAGAUGAUGCUGAUAUUAUAAAGAGUUAGUCACUGCUGCUAAGCAUGGAGGACUAUAUACAUAAGCUCGUUUAUACAGUGUUUGCUUGUGGGAGGGUUUAAUCCUUUUAGGGCCUUGAUGUCAAGAAAAAAAUAACUGGAAACUAUAUUUUGCUAAAGAUAGAAAUGAGGAACUGUGUCAUUUUGGGACAUGUGCAAAUCAUUGAGGAACUCCAUCACCCUGCAUUGAAAAUUGAUUUUUUUUUCCUCUAAAAUGAGAAAGAAACUGAAUAAGCAAUCUGUUGCCUCUUUACUCAUUCAUCACAAUAUCCUGAUUCGUCAUAAGGCUAUCAGUAUAUAAGGGCUAGAAAAUAAUCAUAGCAUUAAGAAGGAAGGAGUCUAUCAUUAUGCUUGAAUUCUGGCAAAUGUCAUGAAUAAGGGUUGGGUCAUAUUUACUUUAAUAUGAGACAAGAUUUAUGUGAUAAGCAAAGGCAUAUAAGGCUGCUCUUUUGAACAGAACAUUUCAGUUAUCAGGCUGUACUAUUACAAGAGAUAAGAAGACAAUAAGGACAAUGUAAUCACAAACAGUGGGAUUCCAUUUGUUUAUUGUACACCAGCUACUUUGUGGGUAUGGUUCCUGACUCCUCUUCUACAUGAGGUUUGGGAAAAAAGUCUCAAACCAAAUGGAACAGUGAAAGGGAAAGUAAUUCAUCUAGCACAUAAGAAUAGUGAUUCAAAACCAAUGCAGAAUAAAUUUCCAUGGGUCAAUAACAUAAGGUGUCAGUUCAGUGUUACUAGAGAUAUGCAAGGCAUAAAAUAUUUUCAUCACCCCAUCACUAAUAACAUGAAAAGCUCAGACAUAGGAUUUCCCAAAUUGAAAUGAAAACACAUUCAUGCCUGCAAAAAUAAUUCUCCUUCUGCUUCAUUUCUCAUUACUUUAUCUAAUAUAAACACAAAUGUAAACAAGGUAAUGGUCUUCAUGUAAAAUGACCAUAUAGUUAAGAAUUUUAGUAAAAUAUUGUUGUUCUGUGUAUUAUUAAACAAAUGCAAUGAAGUAUUAAAAUAGCUGAUCAGUUUGAAUUUCCUGUAAAGCAGUAAUUCCGCAUCAGAAUUGUAGAUAAGGUUGUGAAUUUAUUGACUCAUUUCAGAACAGUGUCUGUUGACAUGGCAGUCAGAGCAGGUGAAUACAGAUGCUCUUUCUGAUUGCAAAGGUUAUAGAGCUAAAUUAGACAGCAUUAUGUGAUACUAGCAAAGACAACUUCUGUUAUAAAUCAGAGGGCAAGGCUUUUCUGAAUCGAUGUGAUAAAUUACUAAGUAAUGAUUACCAAAAAUAAUUACUAAGUAAUAAAAGAUACAGACUGGUUUACUGAAAUAAGCAAGUGUUACAUUUAAUAAUUACCUAUAAUCUUUUUUUGUUAACACAUAAGCAAGUGUUACCUUUAAUAAUUACCUAUAAUCUUUUUUUGUUAACACAUAAUUUGGCCAUUUCAUAUACUGUGUACCUAUUUUCAUUCCCUCUCUGUGGGUCAUUAAAAAACACAAUGUGGUGGAUAAGAACAUUGUCCAAACUUCACUGCUAGUUCCAAUACAUAGAUGAUGGUGUGUAAACUGGAUUGUAGGGGUAGUCAUAUUUGCAAGUUCUACAUGUUAUGCUAAUAUAUCUAGUAUGGUACACAUACACGCCCACACUUUGUGGAUCUUACAGUGGAAUAAAUAGUGUGUCCAUAUUAACUAAACUCAAAGUGCUAUCUGAAGAGGAAUGGAUGUUAUAAGCAGACAGACAGACUGAGUUAAACUGAGUCAUGAAAAAAUAUAUAUUUUAAAGUUUUUGGAAUCAUUUCCAGAAACUAAUAAAGGGAAUUAUUUACUGGUAGUAUUGAGUCUGUGAGAUUGUAGUAUAUACUGAAACAAUCUUCUGGAUGGUGGUAAGGUCUUUUUUAGCAAACACAGUAAAGAGCUUAUUUCAUUUCUGAUGCUUUCAAGGGCAUAUUCCAAAGUAUCACAGAUGUCAAAUAGAAUAUGCUAUAUAAACCAAAAAUGUGCAUUUCAGAUGACCUAUUACAGCAAUCUCAGCCAAUAUGUAAUAUCACAAAAUGUGUCAAGUCAAUCAUAUAAGAGGAUCUAAUCAUUCGGCUGUAUUUCAUGUACCUUCAUGUUGUUGAUAUAUUGUGACCACAGGAAAUAGGUGCCAGAGCAUAUGCAGUUAAGUUACAGGCUCCACGUUGCCUAGGAGGGAAUCAUAACUACAUCAGAAAAUUUUUAACAGUUAUAUCUUAAAAAUUAGAAUUUUAUGUAAUAAAUAAAGCGGCAACCAGGAAUAGCAACGCAACAAAUAUGAAAGCUAAUUAUUAUAUUUAGCUUUCAUAUUUAUAUAAUAUGAUGGAAAUGGAGGAGGAAAAAUGAGUCUUUUGUUAAAUAUAAAGACAAACUAUAACACUCCUUGAUAAUACAACUGGAAAUUUUACUUUAGCAAGCAUAAAAUAGUGGAGGAAAAAAAUCCAACUUCAAGCUCUUUGCACUAGUGAUGAUUAUGUGAUAUAUCAAUGUAAUAUUUAGCCAGUGGUCAUUAGAUGUUACUGUGCUUAAACACAUCUGAUACUCAUGCAUUGCCUUACAGGCUAAAAAUGUAAGAGGUAGGUGUUCAGUAACCUCAAGUUGGAAAGAUAUAUAAUGUUAGAAUCCCCUGAGACAAGCCAUUUCCCUGAAAUAGAAAUUUACCUCAAUACUCAUGUAAUCUAAGACACUUGGCGUAGUAGCAAAGAAGUUGCCUUCAUGUUCUAGUCUCAUCUAAUUGUGACCUUUGUCUUUCAUGUACUUCUGAAAUCAUUUUCCACUUUUUCCACUGGUGUGAUUUUGAAACAAUUCUGAAAUAUUUCAGGUAAGAUUAAUAACAUCCAAUUACAAAUAUAUGUUUCAAUAUUUUAUACGUAUGUCUACUUUGAAAGUUAAACCAAUAGUAUAGAAAGCCUAAGAAUGAACACUGAUUGGACAUACUCACAGAAAUUAAGGGAAAAACACAUAUUGUAAAAUUCCUGUCAAUGUUUGAGUAGAAUACAGAAGUACAUAGCAGUCUUCAAUUUUUAAACACAAUUAUGGGCUUAUAACUGGACGUGACAUGCAUCAUUUAUUAGAACAAUAUUAUUUAUUUAUACUAAGUAAGGAUAUAAGAUCACAGAAGCUUAGUGUUAUAACGGAGACUUCACAGACAUUCAUAACUAAUGUUUUCUAAGGCAAAUAAGGGCAUAAACCAGAACUCAUGGUCAGUGCAGAGUAAGUAUAAAAAGUUAUGUAUGAAAGACAUUUAUUUAUAGAGAUUUCUGAGGAUUCUAUGCCUUUUCAACUUAAAGAUGAGUGUGUCUUAGAAUUUGUUUUAUGCAUCAUUGGACUGGGGAUGAUAUUCAAAUGUGCACUCAGCGUGUCCUCACAUUAAAGGGCACAUUGAACAGUAUAGGAAAAUACAUCAUAAACUAGAAUGUUGUACAGAUUCAUAUAACUUUCCCAUGUGCUCUGCUGUAGAGCUGAAUUUAUAUGCCCUUAAAAAGGGAUAAGAAUCAAUUAAAUAUAAAUACGGAAAUAUACUUAUGUUAGGUCACUUAGCUUCAGAGCAAGAUGUCAUUAACCUUUAUUUCACAGAGAAAAACUGGAAGAAAAGAAUGGUGAACAAGAAUAAAAUGAUAAACUUUUUGGCUUAUAGAGAUGUUUCUUGGGAAUUUUUUCCACUUGUUUUUAUACAUGAAAAAAAUAUCAGUCACAAUACAGACAUUUCUGUAGUAUUUGGUCUGUGGGUAAACUGGAUCCCAGGCAGAAUACUUUUUGACACAGGCCUUUUUAUACAUGCUUUAUAUAUGAUGAAGCUUUGGUGAGAUGUGACUGCAUGGUAGGAUGCAUUUUCCUAGGAUAGGAUAUGGUGCUGCUUGUACUUGCCACCUUUUAUAUGAAUGUAUGUCGCUACAUUGGCCUGUCUUGCCAAGACAUGGUUGAAUGAAGCCUGGUGUGAGCUGUCUAUUUGAAAAGUCACUAGGAUGCAUGUUUCAUUUGCCGUUACAUAAUGCCAAUUUGAACCUGUUUCCUCUAUAUAUUAACAAUCCAAUUGUUAAGAUAAAAUAUACUUUGCUUGAAUGAAUGAUUUUGGUAGUAAUAUGAGCGUUAUCCUUAAAUCAAUGUUACAAUUUUUGCUAUUACUGAAAUACCGUCACAGAGGCCACAUUAUUGGCUGUCUAUACCAUUGCCUGAGUAAAAUUAGGUUUUUAGGUCUUUUUGGCAUUUACUUCUUUUACAGCUGAUGUGGAAUCAAUUAUUCCUUUAUAUGUUCAUAAGUACAAAAUUUCACUAUCUUAAUUACUUCCAAACAAACAAUUUCCAAGCAAGGGUAUGUGUGCCUGGUUUUUCUGCUCCUCCAAUUCUAAGAUCGUUAUUUGUUUGCCUUCUGUUUCUCACCCAAAAAUACAGAUGGUUGGGAAAGAUACAUCUUAUUGAGUUGUCCUAUGCAGUCUCUGUCUAUAUUUGCAUUUCUUUCUAUUCCUAUCUUGCCUUUUUUUUUUUUUUUUACACAGAUUUGGUUUUCCCUUCCCUUUGUGAAAACCAGAAUUGAGCAGCAUUGUACAUCAGAGAUGGUACCCAGGAAAUGUCUUUGUUCCUCAGUAUUUUUCGUCAAAACUUCCAUGCAAAGACAGUCCCAGCAAAGUUGACAUACAUCCCAACCUCUCUCAUUGGCUUUUCUAACUUUUUAUAGAGCUAUUCCCCUGAGAAAAGUGAAAUGCUGAGUAUGAUGGGUAUUGCCUGUUGAUAGGAUAGCUAAGGAAAUUUGCUUUUGGAGAAUGUAUCUUAAAUAAUUAUACAGGAAAGUAGUCACAGUAUAGUGUUCUGUUUAAGGUACAUCAUGGGUACAUAAAUGCCUAAAACCUUCAUCCUUUGGUCUAUUUCUCUGUAAGUGUAAAUUACAUAUAUAUUAGAAAGAGAGAUAGAAUCAAAGAAUUAGGGGUGUUACAGAGGCAGCUUUUUGCUGCCUUGGUUUUGACUGUAUCAGCAUUUCUAUUGCAGACCUCUAUUUUCAGGGGUUUUAGAGACUCGACCAUAAAAAUUUGUUUCAGGCUUAAAAGUUUUGAAAGAUUUUUUUAGGUAUCUGAUUUUAAACAAAUAGAUCUUGUUUUUAUAUUAUAGGAGGGAAAUAAAUGGAGUUUACUAGUUCAAUUUUGCGCUAAUAUAACUUUUAAUAAACUUAACUUUUUAAACAAAAACAUAAAAUCUAAUUAGUUCAUAGUUGGUUGAUGCUUUUUUAAAAGAAUCAAUUAUUGACCUUGAGAAACUUGCCUGCUUCAUCAGUAUAGUAACCUAUCUUUAAGAUAUUUUAAAACGUGUAUACCUUUAUUAACAUUAUCUUGAUUCCAGCGGUGGAUCAGUAUGAUAAUGCAGAUUUAUGACAUCCAUAUAAGCUAUCUGGUAAUAUAGAUUUAGGAAUAUAUAGUAUAUAUGAUACAUAUAUAUAUAUAUAUUUACUAGAUAGAUUAAGGAGAAAAAGCUCCCAUAAACUUAGUUUGUCAAAUAAAUACCAUAUAUUUAAAAAAUGCACAGACAUUUAUCAUUCAGAGUCAGAAUGAGAUUCAAGUAAUUGCAAAGGGAAGUUGUCUCUUGGGUAAACAAUACACAUUUUAUAGCUUCUUGUGAAACUAAUUUUUUCCUUUCUAUAUUGUGGUUAUGGGAAAGUAAAAGAAUUAAAAUUAAUACAGACUUUAUUUAAAUAACAUUAAACUGUGAAGCAGAGAGAAACGCCAGGAAAUUAAAUAUUUAGGCCAUUAUCUUGUGGUUGUCUGACAAUACUUCACCUUUCUUUUAAUUCCCCAUGAUGUUUUCAAUUAUGGAGAGAGUAUUAAAAUCUAGAUUUAAGUUUCUGCAUUGUUCUCAUUACACUCAACACUAUUUCAUUAAGUUCUUGAUAAUAUGUAGUCUUCUGUGUGCAAGGAAAGAAAUAAAUAACACAUUUAUUUGCUGAAUGAGUUUUAAGGUGUGCAAGUUGUAGUGAUGUUUUUCCCACACAGGAUUCUAUACACUUAUACCAUCUUAAAUCUGGCAUUUUUUUUUUCAGAUAGCUUCUACUGACAAACACAAAGCUUGUUUGUGUGCAAAUAUAAGGCUAAAUAAAUGGUGCUAAAGUGUAUUAUGACUGUCAGAUAAAAUCAGGCAAAAUUUUGUGGUGCUUAAAUUAAUUUUUUCAUUGAUUUUAUUGAUCAGUGCAUUGAACAGUGUUUAUUAUUCACAAGUUGUCUUUUAUUAGUAAAUCAAGGCCUCAUAGCACAUUGUUAAAUAAAGUGGUUGACUAGUCUAUGUAACAGCUCACCAAGCUACUAUCUCUUUUAACUCCUUAUAAUGUUGCGUCAUUAAAGGUCAAGGGGUCAUGCUAUUAAUCUCAUUGCUAUAGACCAUUAACAUGACUGAACUUUUCCACAAAGUACUUAUGUUUACAAUGCUAUAACCCUUUGACUGCUGCGGCAACCUUUAACCACACAAAUGUCACAAGCUAGAAUCAUCAGCAUGGUUCUUGCCAUGGCAAUCAAAGAGUUAAGGGCUGUGCAGUGAUUUGUUUUGUAUUUAUUAAUUUAUAUUUAUUUUGUUUCCAUUCAAGGAGGGGAUUAGGGGUGGGGCAGUUUUUGUCUGCUGUAAGUGUCUUAACCUAGGGAAGGGUUAAAUGGCUUUUUAUACUAUUGCAUCUUCUGUAUUUACCAUCAAUUCAUUGUGUUGUAAUUAAAAGAAACUGUCAAUAAAUAAGAGAACAGAAAAA